AGUCGGCCUGCGCUCCUCAGCCUGGCGGUUCUACCUCCGAGGGUUCGCCCGCCCUUGGUUUUCCUUACACCUUAGCCUUUGGCUCCUUUGACCACUCGAAGCCCCACAGCGUGUUCCAGCGGACUUCACCAGCAGACCCAGAAGUGGUGGGUGAAACACUGCCUCUGUUCCUCCUUGAGCCUGUCGGGAGCUGCUGCCUGCCACCACCAUGUCUGCUGCAAAUCCUGAGACUCCAAACUCAACCAUCUCCAGAGAGGCCAGCACCCAGUCUUCAUCAGCUGCAGCUAGCCAAGGCUGGGUGUUACCAGAAGGCAAAAUCGUGCCAAACACUGUUUUUGUUGGUGGAAUUGAUGCUAGGAUGGAUGAAACUGAGAUUGGAAGCUGCUUUGGUAGAUACGGUUCAGUGAAAGAAGUGAAGAUAAUCACGAAUCGAACUGGUGUGUCCAAAGGCUAUGGAUUUGUUUCGUUUGUUAAUGACGUGGAUGUCCAGAAGAUAGUAGGAUCACAGAUACAUUUCCAUGGUAAAAAGCUGAAGCUGGGCCCUGCAAUCAGGAAACAAAAGUUAUGUGCUCGUCAUGUGCAGCCACGUCCUUUGGUAGUUAAUCCUCCUCCUCCACCACAGUUUCAGAACGUCUGGCGGAAUCCAAACACUGAAACCUACCUGCAGCCCCAAAUCACGCCGAAUCCUGUAACUCAGCACGUUCAGGCUUACUCUGCUUAUCCACAUUCACCAGGUCAGGUCAUCACUGGAUGUCAGUUGCUUGUAUAUAAUUAUCAGGAAUAUCCUACUUAUCCCGAUUCAGCAUUUCAGGUCACCACUGGAUAUCAGUUGCCUGUAUAUAAUUAUCAGCCAUUUCCUGCUUAUCCAAGAUCACCAUUUCAGGUCACUGCUGGAUAUCAGUUGCCUGUAUAUAAUUAUCAGGCAUUUCCUGCUUAUCCAAAUUCACCAUUUCAAGUCGCCACUGGAUAUCAGUUCCCUGUAUACAAUUAUCAGGCAUUUCCUGCUUAUCCAAAUUCACCAGUUCAGGUCACCACUGGAUAUCAGUUGCCUGUAUACAAUUAUCAGGCAUUUCCUGCUUAUCCAAAUUCACCAUUUCAAGUCGCCACUGGAUAUCAGUUCCCUGUAUACAAUUAUCAGGCAUUUCCUGCUUAUCCAAAUUCACCAGUUCAGGUCACCACUGGAUAUCAGUUGCCUGUAUACAAUUAUCAGGCAUUUCCUGCUUAUCCAAAUUCACCAUUUCAAGUCGCCACUGGAUAUCAGUUCCCUGUAUACAAUUAUCAGGCAUUUCCUGCUUAUCCAAAUUCACCAGUUCAGGUCACCACUGGAUAUCAGUUGCCUGUAUACAAUUAUCAGGCAUUUCCUGCUUAUCCAAAUUCAGCAGUUCAGGUCACCACUGGAUAUCAGUUCCAUGUAUACAAUUACCAGAUGCCACCGCAGUGCCCUGUUGGGGAGCAAAGGAGAAAUCUGUGGACCGAAGCAUACAAAUGGUGGUAUCUUGUCUGUUUAAUCCAGAGAAGAGACUGAUAAAUUCCGUUGUUACUCAAGAUGACUGCUUCAAGGGUAAAAGAGUGCAUCGCUUUAGAAGAAGUUUGGCAGUAUUUAAAUCUGUUGGAUCCUCUCAGCUAUCUAGUUUCAUGGGAAGUUGCUGGUUUUGAAUAUUAAGCUAAAAGUUUUCCACUAUUACAGAAAUUCUGAAUUUUGGUAAAUCACACUGAAACUUUCUGUAUAACUUGUAUUAUUAGACUCUCUAGUUUUAUCUUAACACUGAAACUGUUCUUCAUUAGAUGUUUAUUUAGAACCUGGUUCUGUGUUUAAUAUAUAGUUUAAAGUAACAAAUAAUCGAGACUGAAAGAAUGUUAAGAUUUAUCUGCAAGGAUUUUUAAAAAAUUGAAACUUGCAUUUUAAGUGUUUAAAAGCAAAUACUGACUUUCAAAAAAGUUUUUAAAACCUGAUUUGAAAGCUAACAAUUUUGAUAGUCUGAACACAAGCAUUUCACUUCUCCAAGAAGUACCUGUGAACAGUACAAUAUUUCAGUAUUGAGCUUUGCAUUUAUGAUUUAUCUAGAAAUUUACCUCAAAAGCAGAAUUUUUAAAACUGCAUUUUUAAUCAGUGGAACUCAAUGUAUAGUUAGCUUUAUUGAAGUCUUAUCCAAACCCAGUAAAACAGAUUCUAAGCAAACAGUCCAAUCAGUGAGUCAUAAUGUUUAUUCAAAGUAUUUUAUCUUUUAUCUAGAAUCCACAUAUGUAUGUCCAAUUUGAUUGGGAUAGUAGUUAGGAUAACUAAAAUUCUGGGCCUAAUUUUUUAAAGAAUCCAAGACAAACUAAACUUUACUGGGUAUAUAACCUUCUCAAUGAGUUACCAUUCUUUUUUAUAAAAAAAAUUGUUCCUUGAAAUGCUAAACUUAAUGGCUGUAUGUGAAAUUUGCAAAAUACUGGUAUUAAAGAACGCUGCAGCUUUUUUAUGUCACUCAAAGGUUAAUCGGAGUAUCUGAAAGGAAUUGUUUUUAUAAAAACAUUGAAGUAUUAGUUACUUGCUAUAAAUAGAUUUUUAUUUUUGUUUUUUAGCCUGUUAUAUUUCCUUCUGUAAAAUAAAAUAUGUCCAGAAGAGGCAUGUUGUUUCUAGAUUAGGUAGUGUCCUCAUUUUAUAUUGUGACCACACAGCUAGAGCACCAGAGCCCUUUUGCUAUACUCACAGUCUUGUUUUCCCAGCCUCUUUUACUAGUCUUUCAGGAGGUUUGCUCUUAGAACUGGUGAUGUAAAGAAUGGAAGUAGCUGUAUGAGCAGUUCAAAGGCCAAGCCGUGGAAUGGUAGCAAUGGGAUAUAAUACCUUUCUAAGGGAAACAUUUGUAUCAGUAUCAUUUGAUCUGCCAUGGACAUGUGUUUAAAGUGGCUUUCUGGCCCUUCUUUCAAUGGCUUCUUCCCUAAAACGUGGAGACUCUAAGUUAAUGUCGUUACUAUGGGCCAUAUUACUAAUGCCCACUGGGGUCUAUGAUUUCUCAAAAUUUUCAUUCGGAAUCCGAAGGAUACAGUCUUUAAACUUUAGAAUUCCCAAGAAGGCUUUAUUACACCUCAGAAAUUGAAAGCACCAUGACUUUGUCCAUUAAAAAAUUAUCCAUAGUUUUUUUAGUGCUUUUAACAUUCCGACAUACAUCAUUCUGUGAUUAAAUCUCCAGAUUUCUGUAAAUGAUACCUACAUUCUAAAGAGUUAAUUCUAAUUAUUCCGAUAUGACCUUAAGGAAAAGUAAAGGAAUAAAUUUUUGUCUUUGUUGAAGUAUUUAAUAGAGUAAGGUAAAGAAGAUAUUAAGUCCCUUUCAAAAUGGAAAAUUAAUUCUAAACUGAGAAAAAUGUUCCUACUACCUAUUGCUGAUACUGUCUUUGCAUAAAUGAAUAAAAAUAAACUUUUUUUCUUCAAAUGUG